CACCAUGCCUGGCCCUGGCCAGCUAUUUAUUACUAAUUCAAUUUUGGAGCUUGUUACUGGUCUAUUCAGGGAUUCAAUUUCUUAUUUGUUCAGUCUUUGCAGGAUGUAUCAUUGUUCCAAGGUUAUAAUCCUCAAGCUUGGCCCUGACGAACUCUCUAAUUAUAUUCAUGUUUCCUCAGUUUUUUCCUUUUAGGUAGACAUAUUAAUAGAAUGGGCUAGAGGAGCCUCUAUGAAGGGAUCUCUCCUUUGAUUGUACUCUGCUUGCUGUAACACCCAAGAAUGCAGAGUCAGGCUAACCCCACUUAGAAUCUGCACAUAGGGUCAGGCCUCUGCCUGGGAUUUACAAGACAGGGCCAGACUUUCAAUUGUGAAUGUAAUGAAAACCAACAAAAUGCAUUUUCUGCAUUGUGAGAUGUCAACAUAGACAUCUUAAAGCCCCCCUUUGAGAGUGUGGCUUUUUAAGCUUUUCAGAUCUUGUUUAGUGACCUGCUACAGUUAUAUGAGAGGCUCCAGGUAUAAAUAGAAUCUGAUGACAGAAUCUAUAAGUGUAAACAAGCAUCUUAAGAGUGAGGGAUAAGGCCACAAAGUAUCCAGAGCUAUGACCACAACUAUACCUACCUGUAAAUUGUAAUAAUGGAGUAGAGUAUUCUUGUCCUUCUUACCCAAAAGCUAGCACAUCAGGAUAGGUGAUCCAGGUUCUGGAGUUCCACCAAAGCAGUUCCAUUUUCUAUUUAGAAUCAGCAUGAAUCUCUCUCAGCCUGGCUUAUCACUGGGCCAUCAGCCUUGAGUCACUGAGAACCGUCUCACAAUCACCUAGGUGUCUUUAAGACAUUUGAGGAUGUCAGGGACAGAAUUGUGUCGGGAUUACAUGGCCAAUUUGCAGAAAUCUCUUUACUUGUGCUCUCUCCACAGGUUCUGUGUAUUGUUCUAGGUGAAAGUAUUCAUGUUUUAAUUGUGUCUCAUGUGACUCUUAAGGUGAGGACAGAAUUAAGUGUGUGGGGUUCAAGAUAGAUUCAUGAGAGUUAAGUUUCACCUUUGCACUAAAAGGUGGUCACAGGAACUGUUCCGUUUGGUUUUGAUAGGAAGAGGUCAGUGUCACCCAUAUUUUCAUUACUAUAGCAGAAAUUGCUGGUGUUUGUGGCAAGGGCAGGCACAUGAAGACAAAUAGAGAAACAUAUUUUUAUAUUCAUUGAGCAGCUCAUUGUUCCUGAAUCUCUCCUGUUAUAAAGGACAAAAGUGAGUGGGCUUUUUCUGCAGUUCUUCUUUUUUUCUGUGGUUGUGAGGCUAGCAGGUAAAUAGGUGGUGCUGACUUCUUUACAAGAAUUUUCUCAGGAUGCAGGUGUAACUUCUCCAGAGAAUGUCAUCUGAAAAGGAUUUCCAAAGAAGGCAAAAGAGGAAAAAUGGCUUUUUUUUUCAGCUAAAUAUGUCUCAGAUGAAGAGCUGUGUCCACUCUGCCUCCUGGAUUGCCAUGCGUUUAGUCCUUGCAAACCUUUACUUCCCUACUUGUGUUUCUUUCCCCUAAUGAGUUUGUUUUAACUACUUUAGAAAAUUCUUGUGAUAGUCAAGGGUCUCUGCAAAAUAUCUCUCUCCUAUAUCCCAGAACCUUCUCUACACUCUCUAAAUCAUGGCUUCUUAUACGCCAUGCAGAAUUCUUAAAAUGAAUUUAUAAUCUGCACUACUUAAAAUGUUCCCUUUGUUGCCAUUGAACGUGGGAAAAUGUAGAUAUUCAAGAUUCCCAUUGGCGGAAAGCUGGGGUCCUUAGUAAAGAUAAAUAACAUGUAAUGUUGUGGUUUCAUCUGUUUUCUCCAUUAAUUCUAUGCAGAACAGGAUUAAUAAAAUGCUUAUUUAAACAGGAUGGUGUUUAUUACCCUGAAAGUUCUGAAAAAAAGUUAUUGAGAGAUACCUGCUCUCUCAGGUGCUAAAGAAAGACUACUUUAAAAUGUUAUUAAAAAUUGCAGAACAUAGAAGAUAUCUGCAUUUUGAACUCUGCAUAAAACUGAUUUUUCUGUAUGGUUAACCUCAGACUAUAAUUUACUUUUUGAGGGGCAAUAUCUCAGCAGUGAUGAUGUCUUCUUCUGUGUGCAUCAGCACAUCAUAAACAUUUGUCCUAAUGCAGUUGAUUUUAAAAUUUACUUAAAAGAGCUCUCUGAAAUAUUUAUUUCACUAUAGAGUUAAUUAUUUUUCUCUUCAUUAUUAAGUAUCUUUAUGUAGCUAAGGAAGAGCUGUGCAUAAACCAUCACAUUUAAUCUGGCAGCUGCCUUUCUUUGUUAGGUUUUCCUUGCAUUUAUCUGUCUUUGGAAAAUGAAGACUCUUAUCUUUGUUUACAGGGCAGAAAAAUUGAGUAAAACACAGGAUCUUCCACUUACUGGAUAUUGACAAAAUAUUCUUUCUGGGCCAAACACAUUGGCAUUACUAGUGAACUUGUUAGAAAUUCAGAAACUCAGAGUUUAUUUCAGAUCUUCUGGGAAAAAAGAAUCUGCACAAGAUCUCCAGUUUACUGUUCACAUUAAAACUUGAGAGGUGCCUUCUAACUCAACAUAUCUUUUGUCUGAAAAAUAUACACAACUCAUUCUUUGUGUGGCAAAUAUAGCACUAAAAAAUGUACAUGUUUGUGUUUAUGCCUUUAGCUUUAUACUUUACUAUUAAUAAAAGUAUAUAUACAGUGGUGUUGUAGAUCUUAUACCAUUCUCUUCUCUCAGAGUUAGAGAAUACAUUAGAGAAUAUUUCUGUGUUGAAAAUUGUUGGAUAAUUUCAGUCAUUCCUGUAAGUCAGAACGAAUUUUCUUUACUUUCUCAUUUGACCUUAAUUCAAAUGAUAAAUUUUGCCCACGUGUAAAUGUGUGUGUGUGUGUGUGUGUUUGUGUGUGUUUGUUUCAGGGGCCGUUGACAUUUAGGGAUGUGGCCAUAGAAUUCUCUCUGGAGGAGUGGCAAUGCCUGGACACUGCUCAGCAGGAUUUGUAUAGGAAAGUGAUGUUAGAGAACUACAGAAACCUGGUCUUCUUGGGUGAGAAUAACUUUAAUACAAAAUCCCUUAUAUACCCUAAAGUUUUCAUUUCUCUGUUUUCAUAGAAUAAUUUUUGGUAAUUUAUGCUUUGCAUAAGUGAGUUUCUGGUGCCUGUUUUAAAGAAAUCUUGAAGAACUGUCCGUGUGGAAAAAAAUUUCUUCAGGAUGUUUUAUCUUGGCCUGAUCUUUUUACAUUUCUGAGCCGGUCUGUAUCCUUCACUCUACAGUAGUGGUAAUUUCAGAAAUUUAGUAGUAUAAAAUAUUGUUGUCCAUAUGUUAAAAUCUAUAUGCCACCACUAAUUUUUUAUCCAUGAAUACUGGGUGGCAAAAUUAAGCACCUACAAAUUUAAAAUAUUUUCUAAAUGUUAAGAACUUUCUGUCAUUAAAUAGUAUUUUGGGAUAAAUUUUCUAGAAUAUUCUAUUACAUCCUCUUUACUAAGCAUGGUACUAGGUAGGUAAUUAGAGAAUAUGAGCAAGAUUCAUGUUAUUUAUUUUUAAUAAAGCAGGUAUUGCUGUCUCUAAGCCAGAUCUGGUCACCUGUCUGGAGCAAGGAAAAGAUCCCUGGAAUAUGAAGGGACACAGUACGGUAGUCAAACCCCCAGGUUUUCUUCCGCCAUCUGUGACAGCUUCUUGAUCUGUCCCAAGGUGGGUGGCUGUGUUCGACGUGUGUUGCUUGUGACGCUUGGGGUUGUCCUCAGCAUCAAUCUUGACAUGGCUGCAACGAGGGGGUCCUCGGGAUCCUCCCAGAAUCUCUUCCUCAGCAUCUGGCUCAUGAUAAAGUUUCAGUUAUAUGUUCUCAUUUUGCUGAAGACUUUUGCCCAGGGCCAGGCAUUAAAGAUUCUUUUCAAAAAGUGAUACUGAGAGAAUAUGUAAAAUGUGGACAUAAGGAUUUACAGUUAAGAAAAGGAUGUAAAAGUAUGAAUGAGUGUAAUGUGCACAAAGAAGGUUAUAAUGAACUAAACCAGUAUUUGACAACUACCCAGAGCAAAAUAUUUCAAUGUGAUAAAUAUGUGAAAGUCUUUCAUAAACUUUUAAAUUCAAAUAGACAUAACACAAAACAUACUGGAAAGAAACCUUUCAAAUGUAAAAAAUGUGGCAAAUCAUUUUGCAUGCUUUUACACCUAUGUCAGCAUAAAAGAAUUCAUAUUAGAGAGAAUUCUUACCGAUGUGAAGAAUGUGGCAAAGCCUUUAUCUGGUUUUCAACCCUUACUAGACACAGGAGAGUUCAUACUGGAGAGAAAUCCUACAAAUAUGAAUGUGGCAAAUCUUUUAACCAGGACUCAAACCUUACUACACAUAAGAGAAUUCAUACUGGACAGAAACCCUACAAAUGUGAAGAAUGUGGCACAUCUUUCUACCAAUUCUCAUACCUUACUAGGCAUAAGCUAAUUCAUACUAGAGAGAAACCCUAUAAAUGUGAACAAUAUGGCAAAACUUUUAACCAAUCUUCAACCCUUACUGGACAUAAGAUAAUUCAUAAUGGAGAAAAACCCUAUAAAUGUGAAGAAUGUGGCAAAGCCUUUAGUAUUUUCUCAACCCCUACUAAACAUAAGAUAAUUCACACUGAAGAGAAAUCCCACAGAUGUGAAGAAUAUUGCAAAGCUUAUAAGGAGUCCUCACACCUUACUACACAUAAAAGAAUUCAUACUGGAGAGAAACCCUACAAAUGUGAAGAAUGUGGCAAAGCCUUUAGUAUUUUCUCAACCCUUACUAAACAUAAGAUAAUUCACACUGAAGAGAAAUCCCACAGAUGUGAAGAAUGUGGCAAAGCUUAUAAGGAGUCUUCACACCUUACUACACAUAAAAGAAUUCAUACUGGAGAGAAACCCUACAAAUGUGAAGAAUGUGGCAAAACCUUUAGUGUAUUCUCAAUUCUUACUAAACAUAAAAUAAUUCAUACAGAAGAGAAACCCUACAAAUGUGAAGAAUGUGGCAAAGCUUUUAAACGAUCUUCAACCCUUACUAAACAUAGGAUAAUUCAUACUGAAGAGAAACCCUACAAAUGUGAAGAAUGUGGCAAAGCUUUUAACCAAUCUUCAACCCUUAGUAUACAUAAAAUAAUUCAUACUGGAGAAAAACCCUACAAAUGUGAAGAAUGUGGCAAAGCUUUUAAACGAUCUUCAACCCUUACUAUACAUAAAAUGAUUCACACUGGAGAAAAACCCUACAAAUGUGAAGAAUGUGGCAAAGCUUUUAAUCGGUCCUCACACCUUACUACACAUAAGAGAAUUCAUACUGGACACAAACCCUACAAAUGUAAAGAAUGUGGCAAAUCCUUUAGUGUAUUCUCAACCCUUACUAAACACAAGAUAAUUCAUACUGAUAAGAAACCCUACAAAUGUGAAGAAUGUGGCAAAGCUUUUAACCGAUCUUCAAUCCUUAGUAUACAUAAGAAAAUUCAUACUGGAGAAAAACCCUACAAAUGUGAAGAAUGUGGCAAAGCUUUUAAGCGGUCCUCACACCUCGCUGGGCACAAGCAAAUUCAUAGUGUACAAAAACCCUACAAAUGUGAAGAAUGUGGCAAAGCCUUUAGUAUAUUCUCAACCCUUACUAAACAUAAGAUAAUUCAUACUGAAGAGAAACCCUACAAAUGUGAAAAAUGUGGCAAAACUUUCUACCGAUUCUCAAACCUUAAUACGCAUAAGAUAAUUCAUACUGGAGAGAAACCUUGCAAAUGUGAAGAAUGUGGCAAAGCUUUUAACCAUUCCUCAAACCUUAUUAAACAUAAGCUAAUUCAUACUGGAGACAAACCCUACAAAUGUGAAGCAUGUGGCAAAGCUUUUAGGCGGUCUUCACAUCUUAGUAGACAUAAGAUAAUUCAUAUUGGAAUUCAUACUGAAGAGACUGUACAAAAGUGAAGAAUGUGGCAAAGGCCUUUACUGCUCCUAUUCCCUUACUAAAGAAUGUGGCAAAGCUUUUCACCAGUACUUUACCCUUAAUACACAUAAGAUAAUUAAUGCUGGAGAGAAACCCUACAAAUGUGAAGAAUGUGGCAAAGAUUUCUAUUGAUUCUCAUACCUUACUAAAUAUAAGAUAAUUCAUAUUGGAGAGAAAUUCUACAGAUGUGAAGAAUGUGGCAAAGGCUUUAAUUAGUUCUCAUCCCUUACUAAACAUAAGAGAAUUCAUACCAUAGAGAAAUCCUACAAAUAUGAAGAAUGUGACAAAGCUUUUAACCACUUCUCAACCCUGCCUACACGUAAGAUAAUUCAUACUGGAAGGAAACCCUACAAAUAUGAGGAAUGUCUCAAAGCUUUUUACUGAUUCUUAUACCUUACUAAACAUAAAAUAAUUCAUAAAGGAGAUAAAUUAUACAAAUGUGAAGAAUGUGGCAAAGCUUUUAACAAAUCCUCAUCCAUUAGUAAACAUAAGAUAAUUCAUACUGGAGAGAAAACCUACAAAUGUGAGGAAUGUGGCAAAGCCUUUAGCCUGUCCCUCCAAUUUACUGCACAUAAGAUAAUUUAUACUGGAGAGAAGCCCUACAAAUGUGAAAAAUGUGGCAAACCUUUUAACCAAUCCUCAACCCUUACUACACAUUAGAUAAUUCAUGCUGGAGAGAAACCCUACAAAUGUGAAAAAUGUGGCAAAGCUUUUAACCAAUUUUCAAACCUUACUAAACAUAAGAUAACUCAUACUGGAGAAAAAUCUUACAAAUGUGAAGAAUGUGGCAAAGCCUUUAUCCAGUCCUCAACUCCUAGUAAACAUAAUUAAUGAUGGAGAGAAACCAUACAACUGUGAAGAAUGUGGCAAAGCUUUUAACCAGUCCUCAAACUUUAUUGAACAAAAUAAUUCAUACAGGAGAGAAACCCUACAAAUGUGAAGAAUGUGACAAAGCCUUUAACCAGUCCUCAAUUUUUACUAAACAUAAGAAAAUUCAUACUGGAGAGAAACCCUAUGAUUGUGAAAAAUAUGGCAAAGGCUUUAACUAGUCCUCAGUUCUUAACACACAUACGAUAAUUCUUACUGCAGAGAAACUCUACAAACCAGUAAGAUGUGACAGUGCUUCUGACAACAUCUCAAACUUUUCUAAUCAUAAAAGAAAUCAUAUUGGUGAGAAAUCCUAGAAAUGUGGAGAAUGUAACAAAGUAUUUAAAUGGUUGUCACACUUGAUUAUAGGUAAUAUUCAUAUUGGAAAAAUUUCCUACAAGUAAGAACAAUGUGGCAAAGUUUUUAACUAAUACACCUUAUUGCACAGAAAAUCAUUUAUAUUUGAGAAAAAUUGUAGAAAUAUAGACUGUGAAAAAGACGUCAAUAUCUGCUCACAUCUUACUAAACACCAGAGAGUUCAUGCUUAAUAAAAGCAUGAUAAGUGCAAUUACUGCCAAAAGAUCUUUCAGAAAAUAUUAUCCUUUAAAGUGAAGGAGAGUAUUUAUAUUAAAGAUGAACAUUACAACCAUAAAGAGGGUUGAAGUACCUUUACUUGUAUCAGAUCUUAUUGUCCACAUUUUGUACUACAGAAAAACUCUGAAGAGGUCACUCAAACUUUGUUCAACAUCAGGGAAUUUAUAUUGGAGAGCUGUCUUGCAAAUGUAAUAAAUUUGGGAAAACAAAUUUUCAAAAACUACAGCUUAGAAAACACCAGAGUUUAUACGAAAAUAUAUUUUCAAAGGUGUAGUAAAAAUAAAAAAAAUUUUAAUCCAAAUUUGUCUAUGUAAAUACCAGAAUUUAUAGUAGAAAUAUAUGAGGAAGCGACACUUCGAAUAUUCUACUAAAUGAGAGUUCUGAGUAUAGAAAAUAAAACUAAAGUUGGUAGAAAAAUUAUUUGUAUAUAAUGUUAAGAGGAGUAAAAGAUUUUUUGUAGAAUAAUAACUAUAUUCGGAUUAUACUUUGUUUCUUGAAAAAAUUACAGAUUUUUUGAAAAGCAAAUGAUGUAACUCAACUCAUUAUUUUCUGCUGUUUCUUCAUUCUUAUUCACUUGUGAAAGCUUGUGAUCAUUUGUUGCUGCAUCAGAGGUAUGAGAGAUUCUUCUUCAUUAGAUGGGCAUUAUUUAUGAUCUUUUCUAUGGAUGAGUAAGAAUAUUAAAAUGUAAGAUGCAUGGUGAAAAUCUAAGUGGAGAGGUUCUUUGUGGUUAACUUAUACUAUUGAGUGAUGCACAAGGUAGGUGUUAAGAGUAAUAUUCUUUUGCAUUAUGAGAAAACUAGUAUAUUAUUCAUAUAUUUUACUAAUUGUACUUUUUUUAUUAUACUUUAAGUUUUAGGGUACAUGUGCACAAUGUGCAGGUUAGUUACAUAUGUAUACAUGUGCCAUGCUGGUGCGCUGCACCCACUAACUCGUCAUCUAGCAUUAGGUAUAUCUCCCAAUGCUAUCCGUCCCCCCUCCCCCCAAUUGUACUUUUAUAUAAUAAAAUGCAGUACAUUUUAAAAAAUUUUAAAUUCUGUGUGAAGGUAACUGUUUCAACAUUUUUAACAUGGUAAAUAUUAUUGUGCAUUCAAUAAAGUGUUGUUAUGCCACAAA